GAACGGCUUCGCGAGUUGGGGCAGCUCCUCGCGCUCGGCCCUGCUCGGCGGCGAGAGCUCCGCCUGGGCGCCGCGUUCCUACAGCCGCCGGAGCCGCCAGGCGCCGAGGGAACGGACAGACCUCCGCGCACCCUUGCCGACCGGGGCGGGCAGAGGCGGGCAAGCGGCGAACGCCUGGGAGCGCGGAGAGCCAGGCCAGCCCGGAGCGCGCCGGGGACACCCUGUGCGCCCCGAGUCCCGGCACCAUGCGACCCGCCGCGCGUCCUCGCGGGCCCGGGGCUUCGCUCUUCGCUCGCUGAGCCCCUGCGCUCGCCACCACGGAAACUCGGAAAGAGGAGGCGAGGCUGUGGGGAGCGGCGCGGAGACGGACUAGACUUCCCCUCCGCCCCCAAGAGGCUGCCGGUCCCCGGUUCCCUGGGCUUCUCCAGCUUUAUCAUGAACCUGGCGCAAGGUUGGCUUUAGGAAAAAUUCUGGAGCCAGAGGGAGAGUCAAGGCAAUUCUUUGGUUGCUAAGUGUGAGUGAAGACACUCAGGAUGGCUCAAGGAUCCGGGGAUCAAAGAGCAGUGGGGGUUGCUGACCCAGAGGAGAGUUCUCCAAACAUGAUCGUUUACUGCAAAAUUGAAGACAUCAUUACAAAGAUGCAAGAUGACAAGACAGGGGGUGUGCCCAUCAGAACAGUCAAGAGCUUUCUCUCCAAAAUCCCCAGUGUCGUCACAGGUACUGACAUUGUGCAGUGGCUUAUGAAGAACCUUUCCAUUGAGGACCCAGUUGAAGCAAUACACUUGGGGAGCCUUAUCGCUGCCCAGGGCUACAUCUUUCCAAUCUCAGACCAUGUUCUCACCAUGAAGGAUGAUGGCACCUUUUAUCGUUUCCAGGCUCCGUACUUCUGGCCUUCGAACUGCUGGGAACCUGAAAACACUGACUAUGCCAUCUAUCUCUGUAAGAGGACAAUGCAAAAUAAAGCAAGGCUGGAACUGGCAGAUUAUGAAGCAGAAAACUUAGCAAGACUCCAGAGGGCCUUUGCGAGGAAGUGGGAAUUCAUCUUUAUGCAAGCAGAAGCACAAGUAAAGAUUGACCGGAAAAAAGACAAGACAGAAAGGAAAAUUUUGGAUAGUCAAGAACGAGCCUUUUGGGAUGUCCACAGGCCUGUGCCAGGCUGUGUGAACACAACAGAAAUGGAUAUCCGAAAAUGUCGACGUUUGAAGAAUCCACAAAAGGUUAAAAAGUCCGUGUAUGGCGUGACUGAAGAGUCCCAGGCACAGAGCCCGGUGCAUGUACUCAGCCAACCAAUCAGGAAAACAACAAAAGAGGACAUCCGGAAACAGAUAACAUUUUUGAACGCACAGAUCGACAGACAUUGUUUGAAAAUGUCCAAAGUGGCUGAAAGUUUAAUUGCCUACACGGAACAAUAUGUGGAAUAUGACCCUUUGAUAACACCAGCUGAGCCAUCCAACCCUUGGAUCAGCGAUGACGUUGCUUUGUGGGACAUAGAGAUGAGCAAAGAGCCCAGCCAACAGCGAGUAAAAAGAUGGGGCUUCUCUUUCGAUGAGAUAUUGAAGGACCAGGUGGGGCGGGACCAGUUUCUACGAUUCCUGGAGUCCGAAUUCAGUUCAGAAAACCUCAGAGCAUGUGCUGCGGGCAAAGGACUGCCCCUCCAAAGUUAAUGUGCAACAUCCAUGCACUUAUUUGAAGUUGAGACCAUCGGUCCCAUACGUCAAUCAAGUGAUAUUUAUGCUACACCUGUGCUGUAUCAAGCCCUGUGAGAGUCUGCUGAGAGAUGCAAGUCAAGAUGUGUGAUCUUUGCCUGUAACGACCUUGUAGGUCCUUGAGGAAAAAACACAAGAAAUGAUUAAAUCAUUGAAUGUCUAUAAAUGAGUGUAAACUCUAAGAACCAUUUCGAAAGCAUUUAAAGGAGAAGAAUCAAAGCUGAAGUAGUUAAAUCAUAAGCUGGACUUUGAAGAAUACACAGGAUAAUAGUAGACGAAGAAGCAGGAGAGAGAAUAUUCCAAGCUGGAGGACCAAAUGAGGAAAGAGGUGGCCGUGGGACUCUCCCACUCCAUAAGGUCCUGAGAGGACACGUAGAUGCCGACUAGCUGUAUGGAGCGUGCUGUUCUAGGCAUCCACGUGUCUGUUAUAAACCAGACAAGGUUGAGUAUCUUAUUUUGGGUUAUUAUACAAGAGCCUUUCCUUGUGCUGAAGCAUGAUUCCAAACACAUCUCAGAGCUUCAUUUCAAUGCCUAAUGAAGCAUUUGUAACAGAAGGCUUGACUUCUAAUACUCUUCACUAGGGUGGUGCUCAGACUAGCCUCCCUGUAUAGGAAGGAAGGCUCUCUGUGGCCAGCUUGAUGGACCCAGGUGGCCUCUCUGUGUAGCCAGCUCAGUCCCAGUUUCCACCCCCUCCAUGGUCCCUAUGAGCCACCCCUGGGAGUCCUUCUCAUCUUCCCUUCUUACCUGUUCCCCUUGGGUCUCCAAGAUGGAGCGGUAUAGAGGCCCCCUUUACCUAACUACCUCUAAGCCCGUAAGUAGCCUCAGGACCCUCUGCUGCCUGCACUCUUGCAGAGAGCUUGAAGAAUGACCCAGAGUUUGGUCAUUGUGAGGGUCCCAGGAGCAUCCACUGGCUCAGCUGCCACCUUGCCUGGUCAGAGCAUUCAUUCUAGAAAGUCCCGAGUGUAGCCAGAACCACAUAUCAGUUCAGACUAGUUUCACAAAUUAUGCAUCACACUUAAAGCCCAGAGUGCACCAAGGAGUGUGUCCCUGGCAGGUGUUCAGUGCUUCUUCCUGCCAUCACCUCCUGCGCCUCUGCCAGCUCCUUUCCCCAUGCCAGGAGGGCUACAUUUAAUCUUGGGUGAAAGCAUGCAUGUGAGCAUGUGUUCAUGUGCCAGAGCCUAAGCCACACCCCCAGAAUGCAGAAAUCCAGACUUCAGAGGGUCACCCCUGCUCCAUGACAGGAAAGGAAAUAGAAUAGCAGGGAGGAAAAGGAUAGCCAAGAGCCUCUAAAAUCCUCUCUGGAUGCCCAAAUUCCAUUUUUAUGAUAUUCAGCAUAACUGGAUACAUGGUGGGUGAGAGAGAAGCUCAGUCGUAAAUCACAUAACUGUAGGACUCUUCAGUCACCCAUCACAGGGCAGCCUUUUCCCCGUUCCAUUGCGUUCAUCCCUUCAGCUGCAGAUAUCAUCUUAGCACCAACCGUGGCACAGGGCUGGCGGAUUUAGAGCUGACUGAGUAAAUAUCAGGGUGGCCAGGCAUGGCUAUACAGAUGCACCUCCACUGUGGCUCAUGCCAUGGAGGCCCCUGGGAGUUGUGCAAUAUGGCACAACUUGAGGAUCCUGCCAACCUGUCAUGUUGGCCGUGCUGGAGUCGUCCCUUCUCCGCAGGAUUGGUGAGGGGCCCAGGCCACUGGCAUUGGAGCAUGGCAGGAAAAAGCCUGACCAGAACUCACCUGGGUAAAUUACAAAGUGCUUCUCCACUUCCUCUGUCCUCCUGUGCUCCCUCUCAUCUCUCCAGUGAAAGGGCUGCUUAGAUCAUAACAUUCUUGCACAACCCACGGGGUGCCAGUUAAGUAGCCAAGUGGCUGAAUUUCUAUCAGAGCUUCAGAAUGCGGAAUGGAGGAGCCCCAAAGUGUCACCCUGGAUCCUUUAAGGAACAAUUUCUAUGAUGAUGUAAUAGAAGUUGACAUCCCCUUUGAUCAGUGUCUUCUGGGUGGGUCUGUGAGAUGAGGGUGGGGGCAUCAUCUCUGUGGACUGGGUGGGGUAUGACCAGCAGCGCAUUUUGCUGAAGCUGUGAGCUCUCUGUGGCAGGGUCUACCUCUUUUUCUCCUUUUCUGACCCACCUGAGCUGGGUGCAGGCUCCCUUUGCACCGAGUGGACCCACAGACAGCUGUUUGUUGAGUGCCUUGGGAAUGCUCAUGGCUUCUGUCCACAAGGCAGGGGCCUCACAGCUCUGAUGCAGGGAGCUCCGCUCAGUUUCUUGGCCUCAUCCUUCUUCCUGCUUUGUGCAUUUUCCCAGAAUAAUGACAGUCACUCCUUCCCAUCUUUGCUCCCUCUCCCACAUCUCCCCUACACAAAUCUUUGUCCUCCCUGGCUUGACACCCUCUGCUGCACAGCAGAGAAUGAGUUAAAAAUCAAAACCCACAGCAAAGAGUGUCCCCCGUACAUUUUUUGUGAGCUGUAACAUCUCCUGAGAGAAGGUAGUUGUUCUUCUAACCUGCAGAUUGAUGAUCCGAGUUCCACACAGUGUCGGCUGAAGGGAGAAGCAAUUAAAAGAGAACACAGUGGGGCACCAGGUUCAUCUCGAGAGCUCUUGUCUCUGGCAGUUGCCCUGAGUCCAAGGAAGACCUCAGAAGGUUCACUAGGCCCAGCAGGAUCCACCACUUACCAAACCCAUGAUUAAUAGGAACAGAGGUGACUCCCACGACACCACAACCAUCUGCAGUGUUUCAGUCACUGCCCAGUGAACAGAACUCAGCUUCAGUGGUGCUGGGGGUGGUUACUAACGUAGGCACCCCGGAAUUUUAGCCCCACCGGGAACUAAACCAAGUUUAAGCUCUGCUGCCUACGUCUCUGGUUGACCAGCAGAGGGCAUAGAAACACUUUCUUCUCUCCUGGAGUUUGCUUUUUCUCUGGGAGCGAACCAAAAGCUGUAUUUUCUAACCCAUGAAAAUUCUAGUUUAUGAAAAGAUAUGUAAACUGGUGACUGAGGGCCUGCCCAGACCUCCUGGUAGGAUGGAGAAUGAUCAAGGGCCAAAUGGUUUGUCUUACCCAGCCAGCCUUGAGAAAAUCCUCUUCCUUGAAAGCCUCUAGGGAGAAAGGAGGCUCCCACUGGGGCAGCCCCUGGAUGGUCCUCCAGCCCUGUUCUCCACUGCUUCGCCCCAGUGGUAUCUGAGCCCAGGCUGCCUCGCUCCAAAAGCUAGUUUCCCCGCCAGCAUUUCUAAGUCAUGAACACGGAUCAAAUGCCCGCACAGGGGCUGCCUCCCUACUGCAGCUAUGACAAUUGGCAGAGACCAGGGGCAGGUCAGGACAGGUGGUCUCCCAGAUAUUAGUCCUUGUGGCCUGCCAGUCACAACGGCCCUUCUGCUGCAAGCCAUGGAGGCUCAGUGCAGGAUGGAUGGAUUUGAUGCAGCUGCUGGCAUUUCACUCCCUGCCGCUGCCCUUGGGGAGGAGCGGUACCUGCAGGUUUUUUAUAAGAGCAGAAGCUUCCAAAGCUUCAAGGGGCUUCCCAUGGGCAGCAGAUGUGCAGAGAGGAGCUGCUGUGGCUCUCUGCAGCGGGGAAUGUGGCCUGGGCUCUGAGUUCCCAGCUCAGGCCUGUGGGGCUCGAAGAUGGCCAACACUAACCAAAGCCUGUUCUGAAUUUCAAAUUGACACAAAGGUUCCUCAAAACCAGUGAUGGUAAACACAUACGGGAUGUCAGGAUGCUGCUGUGACAGCAGUUUUGCUGUUGCCUGAGAGAGACAAGGCAGGUCAACUCCAAGGCAGACAGAAGGCCAGGGAGAGUCCCCAGUGUGUGCAGGGAGAGAAAACUGCUGUCUAGGGAAUGUUACCCCAUACCUUCCCCCUCUCCCUUCUUGCCCUUUCCCCCUCCUUCCCUCCCUUUCUCUCCCCUCCCCUUCCUCUUCCUCCAGCAUGCCUGUUGUUUUCACUUGUACUUAAAAAAAUUCUUGGUUUUAUGUGACAAAGAAAACCUUUUUAUUUUUACAUAAAAGUUUAUUAAAUUUGAUUCCGCGGCCUGGUGCAAUGGCUCACGCCUGUCAUCCCAGCACUUUGGGAGGCCAAGGCGGGCGGAUCACUUGAGGCCAGGAGUUCAAGACCAGCCUGGCCAACAUGGUGAAACCCCAUCUCUGCUAAAAAUGCAAAAAUUAGCUGAGCAUGGUGACAUGCCCCUGUAAUUCCAGCUACUCAGGAGGCUGAGGCAGGAGAAUAGCUUGAACCUGAGAGGCGGAGGUUGCAGUGAGCCGAGAUGUAGCCACUGCACUCCAGUUUGGGUGACAGAUCAUGACCCUGUCUCAAAAAAAUUGAUUAUGAAAUUUGUAUUUCCAUCAGCUCCGGUCAUCUCUAUAUCCAGCUGAGUGAUGUACAUUUUCAUGUGGCACCCAAAUCAUCCUGCAAAAAGGACCCUGAGCCCUCAGGAACCGCAGGGAGCCUGCAGAGCUCCCAGGGUCCUCAGGGCCUUCCCACAGGGGCUCAGCAGCUCCUCCUCAGUGCUGACAGAGGUGACAGAAAGUGACCUCCCAUGUGGCAUUGAUUGAGGGGGCAGGAAAUCACCCAGGUGUCAUCCAUUUGUGUGAGAAGUUGCAGGGGCCCAGGGGGCGUGGGAAGACGCUGACCCAGAAGGUUGCUUCCAGCCAGGGAUUCAGCCCAGACGGCCUCCCUCUGUGAACCUGGUUCUCCUGUCUGCCUAGCAUGGGGCUGAGGAAGCCUCACUGACUUCGUCUCUGGACAUUUGACCCCUUCUGGGCCUUGGAAAAGCCAACACUGGCUUCUUCCUAUAGAGCCAGGUUCCCCGCAUCUUUCACCUACUGGUCAGACAUGGCCUUCCAGGCAGAGAAAGCCUUGUAGGUACUCUCACCAGCAGAUGGCCAUUUUCACUUGGCAAGCCUCCCGGCCACUUCCUUCUUUUCACAGCAGACCUGAGAGAGUGGACAGAGAGCCCUACAGAACCUAGGGCAGGCCUGGGAGAUGGAGGAGACCCAUGCCCCAGCUCAAGAGUCAAGGGCCCACCUGAACAAUGAGGUAGGGGAACAGCUCCUUUCAAGCCCUUCCUUCCCCACCCUCUCUGGACUCUGGAUAAAGAAACACGACUGCUUUCCUCUCACCCAGAAGCCAGAAGGACCUGAGCACCCAGGACUUGUGGCUGUCAGAGAGCUGUGGAAGGGCAGGGGACACCAGAUGGCAGCAGCAAGAGCUGGGCGGCAGCAUCUGCCCAGGCCACCUGCGGAGAGAAGGCUGGAAUCCGAGGGAUCACACUGGGCCAGCAUUGAGCCUGUGGCCACCACACUGACCCCUCCUCAGCUCCCCCUCACAGGACCUGAAAGCAUUUCUGAGUUAAGUCUGCAUAGGAAGUUUUCCAGAGCCAUGCCACAUAUCCCUCCAUCCACUCAGUGCCCAUUUUACAGAUGAAGAGAGAGGCACCCAGAAAGGUACACCAAGGCAAGAUAUGGCGUAGACAGGAUGAGGGCAGAGCCAGCUUCCUGAUCUGAUGGAAGUCAUGAAGCCUUCUCUGCCUUACGCUUGGCUCUGCAGGGUCGCUGAGAGGUUCCUUUAAGGAGAUCAUCAGAAUCCUAAAUGGCAAAAAAUGGCAAAUCAGGGGAAGAGUUGGAGCCCAGCAUUUGGGGACACACACACACACACACAGUCGUCUUGCCUUGCAGAAAUUGGGUUGCAUUACUCCAGUCUGCCACUGAGUGGCACCUUUGGGCCAUGCACUUGGCUCCAAAGACAUUUCUCUGAACAGCAACAGAAAAACAUGUUUAACCCUAAAAAAAAAAAAAAAAGAAACAAGUACAUCUUACUUUGGAUGAAAUUUGAUGACAGAUUGAAUGCACUGUCUGCACUUUCCACCACGUCAUGUUUCAGCUUCGCUUGUCCCUCCCUUUCUGUUGACUAGACUACCUGUGAUUCCCGCUGCUCUCGGAACCAGCACAGGACCUACUCUCUUACUCACUGAUGGGGGAGCUGGCCUGUCCAUGCACAGGGCAAAGGAUAUGACACCCAGACCUGGAUCCUGCUGCAAGGCUGCCUUGGGAACCAUCCUUAAGACCCGGUAGCUGUUGUCCAAGCUUUGGCUCUGGCUGCUGCUGCUCUCAGCAGAAAAGAGCUCACUGCUCCCAUGCGGAUGCUGAGGGAUUAAACAGAGGCAAAUACGGAAGUGAGCAGAUUUUUCUCUCUUGCUCUCAGCAGAAGGAGAACCAUUCUGCAGAGAAGUUUUCAACAUAUGCCUCUUCAGCAUUGCUCCAGAUGCGUCCGUCUUCACUCUGAAACCCAUAUAUUGAGCACCUACUAUUUGCCAAGCACCGUGCUGAGCACUGAUGUGAAUUGGCUCAGUUUCUCCAUCUAUAAUAGGAAUGGCUGGUUCAUUCUUACACAGAUAGUCUUUAUGAUUCCAGGACACUGCCUGCUUCUGGGAUCUCUCCUCCAUUUUGAUGCCAUCACUUGAUCCCAACUAGAUUUGACAAAGGGUCUCACACUGUCUGCAUGGUGGCAUGUAUGUAGCACUGGGGUUCUCAACCAGGAAUGAGUUCAUCUCCCAGGGGACAUUGGGCAAUGUUUGGAAACAUUUUUAGUUGUCAUAACUUGGGAAGGGGGGUUGCUAUUGGCAUCUAGUGGGUAGAGGCCAAGGUUGCUGCUAAACAUCCUACAUUUCACAGAAUAGCCUCAACAACAAAGAAUUAUCCAGCCUGAAGUGGCAAUAGUGCUGAGGUUGAGAAACCUUCAUGUAGAAGGAGAGAAAUCCCGUUCUGAUAACGAGAAGCACAUUGAUCUUUUAAUAUGCAAUUCUUUUCUGUUCUGCACCAUAGGAACACCUUUGAUGUUUUCACAAUCUCCAUGGUCUUUGCAGCUCAUGUAGUGGCAUCAGGGCAGGCUGAGAGAUGCAGCAGAAUGGGUUUCAUGGGACAUCAGCUCUGGGGCCAUCUCAGGCAACAUCCCGAUGCUGAGCCCCCUGGAACUGACUGUGUUUCUGCUCCCACUUCAGGUUCUGGCUGGCUGUCCAAGAUCUUAAGAAACAACCCCUACAGGAUGUGGCCAAGAGGGUAG